GAGACGAAACUUCCCGUCCCGGCGGCUCUGGCACCCAGGGUCCGGCCUGCGCCUUCCCGCCAGGCCUGGACACUGGUUCAACACCUGUGACUUCAUGUGUGCGCGCCGGCCACACCUGCAGUCACACCUGUAGCCCCCUCUGCCAAGAGAUCCAUACCGAGGCAGCGUCGGUGGCUACAAGCCCUCAGUCCACACCUGUGGACACCUGUGACACCUGGCCACACGACCUGUGGCCGCGGCCUGGCGUCUGCUGCGACAGGAGCCCUUACCUCCCCUGUUAUAACACCUGACCGCCACCUAACUGCCCCUGCAGAAGGAGCAAUGGCCUUGGCUCCUGAGAGGUAAGAGCCCGGCCCACCCUCUCCAGAUGCCAGUCCCCGAGCGCCCUGCAGCCGGCCCUGACUCUCCGCGGCCGGGCACCCGCAGGGCAGCCCCACGCGUGCUGUUCGGAGAGUGGCUCCUUGGAGAGAUCAGCAGCGGCUGCUAUGAGGGGCUGCAGUGGCUGGACGAGGCCCGCACCUGUUUCCGCGUGCCCUGGAAGCACUUCGCGCGCAAGGACCUGAGCGAGGCCGACGCGCGCAUCUUCAAGGCCUGGGCUGUGGCCCGCGGCAGGUGGCCGCCUAGCAGCAGGGGAGGUGGCCCGCCCCCCGAGGCUGAGACUGCGGAGCGCGCCGGCUGGAAAACCAACUUCCGCUGCGCACUGCGCAGCACGCGUCGCUUCGUGAUGCUGCGGGAUAACUCGGGGGACCCGGCCGACCCGCACAAGGUGUACGCGCUCAGCCGGGAGCUGUGCUGGCGAGAAGGCCCAGGCACGGACCAGACUGAGGCAGAGGCCCCCGCAGCUGUCCCACCACCACAGGGUGGGCCCCCAGGGCCAUUCCUGGCACACACACAUGCUGGACUCCAAGCCCCAGGCCCCCUCCCUGCCCCAGCUGGUGACAAGGGGGACCUCCUGCUCCAGGCAGUGCAACAGAGCUGCCUGGCAGACCAUCUGCUGACAGCGUCAUGGGGGGCAGAUCCAGUCCCAACCAAGGCUCCUGGAGAGGGACAAGAAGGGCUUCCCCUGACUGGGGCCUGUGCUGGAGGCCCAGGGCUCCCUGCUGGGGAGCUGUACGGGUGGGCAGUAGAGACGACCCCCAGCCCCGGGCCCCAGCCCGCGGCACUAACGACAGGCGAGGCCGCGGCCCCAGAGUCCCCGCACCAGGCAGAGCCGUACCUGUCACCCUCCCCAAGCGCCUGCACCGCGGUGCAAGAGCCCAGCCCAGGGGCGCUGGACGUGACCAUCAUGUACAAGGGCCGCACGGUGCUGCAGAAGGUGGUGGGACACCCGAGCUGCACGUUCCUAUACGGCCCCCCAGACCCAGCUGUCCGGGCCACAGACCCCCAGCAGGUAGCAUUCCCCAGCCCUGCCGAGCUCCCGGACCAGAAGCAGCUGCGCUACACGGAGGAACUGCUGCGGCACGUGGCCCCUGGGUUGCACCUGGAGCUUCGGGGGCCACAGCUGUGGGCCCGGCGCAUGGGCAAGUGCAAGGUGUACUGGGAGGUGGGCGGACCCCCAGGCUCCGCCAGCCCCUCCACCCCAGCCUGCCUGCUGCCUCGGAACUGUGACACCCCCAUCUUCGACUUCAGAGUCUUCUUCCAAGAGCUGGUGGAAUUCCGGGCACGGCAGCGCCGUGGCUCCCCACGCUAUACCAUCUACCUGGGCUUCGGGCAGGACCUGUCAGCUGGGAGGCCCAAGGAGAAGAGCCUGGUCCUGGUGAAGCUGGAACCCUGGCUGUGCCGAGUGCACCUAGAGGGCACGCAGCGUGAGGGUGUGUCUUCCCUGGAUAGCAGCAGCCUCAGCCUCUGCCUGUCCAGCGCCAACAGCCUCUAUGACGACAUCGAGUGCUUCCUUAUGGAGCUGGAGCAGCCCGCCUAGAACCCAGUCUAAUGAGAACUCCAGAAAGCUGGAGCAGCCCACCUAGAGCUGGCCGCGGCCGCCCAGUCUAAUAAAAAGAACUCCAGAACA